AAAGUGCUGGGAUUACAGGUGUGUGCCAACACACCUGGCCAAGUUGUAUAUACUAUUAAUCUAGGCUAUUUCUGACACUGUUGAUUUUCCUUUUCCCCUUAGGUGAGGCAGGCGACUAAUCAGAUUGUGAUGAAUUGUGCUGAUAUUGAUAUUAUUACAGCUUCAUAUGCACCAGAAGGAGAUGAAGAAAUACAUGCUACAGGAUUUAACUAUCAGAAUGAAGAUGAAAAAGUCACCUUGUCUUUCCCUAGUACUCUGCAAACAGGUACGGGAACCUUAAAGAUAGAUUUUGUUGGAGAGCUGAAUGACAAAAUGAAAGGUUUCUAUAGAAGUAAGUAUACUACCCCUUCUGGAGAGGUGCGCUAUGCUGCUGUAACACAGUUUGAGGCUACUGAUGCCCGAAGGGCUUUUCCUUGCUGGGAUGAGCCUGCUAUCAAAGCAACUUUUGAUAUCUCAUUGGUUGUUCCUAAAGACAGAGUAGCUUUAUCAAACAUGAAUGUAAUUGACCGGAAACCAUACCCUGAUGAUGAAAAUUUAGUGGAAGUGAAGUUUGCCCGCACACCUGUUACAUCUACAUAUCUGGUGGCAUUUGUUGUGGGUGAAUAUGACUUUGUAGAAACAAGGUCAAAAGAUGGUGUGUGUGUCUGUGUUUACACUCCUGUUGGCAAAGCAGAACAAGGAAAAUUUGCAUUAGAGGUUGCUGCUAAAACCUUGCCUUUUUAUAAGGACUACUUCAAUGUUCCUUAUCCUCUACCUAAAAUUGAUCUCAUUGCUAUUGCAGACUUUGCAGCUGGUGCCAUGGAGAACUGGGACCUUGUUACUUAUAGGUAUGUUAAUGAUGUAUUACCCUGCCUUAUCUUUUCAAAUCACUGAUUUCAAAAGGGCUUCCCUCCUAAUCACAGUUGAGUAGCUUCUGCUUUACGAUAUGGUGUAAAUUUUUCUACCUUCCCCCACUUCCAUGCACAUUUCAAGAAUGCAGAUGGACACCUCUCCCUUUGGUGCUACUGUCUGAGGGUGUAAGAUUUUAAAGUGAGCAUCUGGCGGUAGUAGCAUUUUUAGAUAUAUUCUUGGCUAAGUUUCUCAUUGCAGUGCCUUUCUUUCCUGCCAGUAGUUUCAUAGCUAUUUAUCCAGCUUGGAGAACCUUCCCUAAUUUCAUAUCUUCUAGCCAAGUUUUUACAUGUCUGUCACCACAACAUAAACAUGUGAGUUGAAUAACUUUUAAAAGCAGAGUCUGUCUGUAAACAAGUUUUUGCCUUCUACUUUCAAUUGCCUUCUUAGAUGAGCUAAGUGUUGAACGGCCGGCUCAGUGCUGUUUUUGGGACUAUGGAAUGCAUCUUCCUCCACCACUCCCCUCAUUUAAUGAAAGGACUUUCUUCUCUCUCCAUCUAGCACAGUAAUCGCUAAUCCCUUAGACAAUGUUUUCCCAAAAUUUCAGGCAGCUAUUCUAUCAACAAACUGAUAAUUAAACUUGUGUCACAUCUUUGAUAUUCUGUUGUAUUAAUUCUGUUGGGGUAGUCUUUAAUCUUCGUGAAACUUUUUCUUUCCAUAUUAGGAAAUAUUUUCCUAAUAUCUCUAAAGCCUAACUUGUCCAUCUGACUUACUGUCUGAAUCUUCCCAACUUAUGCAUGCCCACUUUUAUUGUUUAAAUUUGUUUCUCUUUUUUUUUUUUUUA